GCUUCAGGCCCCACCGGGGCGCGGAGAGUCCCAGGCCCGGCCGGGACCGGGACGGCGUCCGAGUGCCAAUGGCUAGCUCUAGGUGUCCCGCUCCCCGCGGGUGCCGCUGCCUCCCCGGAGCUUCUCUCGCAUGGCUGGGGACAGUACUGCUACUUCUCGCCGACUGGGUGCUGCUCCGGACCGCGCUGCCCCGCAUAUUCUCCCUGCUGGUGCCCACCGCGCUGCCACUGCUCCGGGUCUGGGCGGUGGGCCUGAGCCGCUGGGCCGUGCUCUGGCUGGGGGCCUGCGGGGUCCUCAGGGCAACGGUUGGCUCCAAGAGCGAAAACGCAGGUGCCCAGGGCUGGCUGGCUGCUUUGAAGCCAUUAGCUGCGGCACUGGGCUUGGCCCUGCCGGGACUUGCCUUGUUCCGAGAGCUGAUCUCAUGGGGAGCCCCCGGGUCCGCGGAUAGCACCAGGCUACUGCACUGGGGAAGUCACCCUACCGCCUUCGUUGUCAGUUAUGCAGCGGCACUGCCCGCAGCAGCCCUGUGGCACAAACUCGGGAGCCUCUGGGUGCCCGGCGGUCAGGGCGGCUCUGGAAACCCUGUGCGUCGGCUUCUAGGCUGCCUGGGCUCGGAGACGCGCCGCCUCUCGCUGUUCCUGGUCCUGGUGGUCCUCUCCUCUCUUGGGGAGAUGGCCAUUCCAUUCUUUACGGGCCGCCUCACUGACUGGAUUCUACAAGAUGGCUCAGCCGAUACCUUCACUCGAAACUUAACUCUCAUGUCCAUUCUCACCAUAGCCAGUGCAGUGCUGGAGUUCGUGGGUGACGGGAUCUAUAACAACACCAUGGGCCACGUGCACAGCCACUUGCAGGGAGAGGUGUUUGGGGCUGUCCUGCGCCAGGAGACGGAGUUUUUCCAACAGAACCAGACAGGUAACAUCAUGUCUCGGGUAACAGAGGACACGUCCACCCUGAGUGAUUCUCUGAGUGAGAAUCUGAGCUUAUUUCUGUGGUACCUGGUGCGAGGCCUAUGUCUCUUGGGGAUCAUGCUCUGGGGAUCAGUGUCCCUCACCAUGGUCACCCUGAUCACCCUGCCUCUGCUUUUCCUUCUGCCCAAGAAGGUGGGAAAAUGGUACCAGUUGCUGGAAGUGCAGGUGCGGGAAUCUCUGGCAAAGUCCAGCCAGGUGGCCAUUGAGGCUCUGUCGGCCAUGCCUACAGUUCGAAGCUUUGCCAACGAGGAGGGCGAAGCCCAGAAGUUUAGGGAAAAGCUGCAAGAAAUAAAGACACUCAACCAGAAGGAGGCUGUGGCCUAUGCAGUCAACUCCUGGACCACUAGUAUUUCAGGUAUGCUGCUGAAAGUGGGAAUCCUCUACAUUGGUGGGCAGCUGGUGACCAGUGGGGCUGUAAGCAGUGGGAACCUUGUCACAUUUGUUCUCUACCAGAUGCAGUUCACCCAGGCUGUGGAGGUACUGCUCUCCAUCUACCCCAGAGUACAGAAGGCUGUGGGCUCCUCAGAGAAAAUAUUUGAGUACCUGGACCGCACCCCUCGCUGCCCACCCAGUGGUCUGUUGACUCCCUUACACUUGGAGGGCCUUGUCCAGUUCCAAGAUGUCUCCUUUGCCUACCCAAACCGCCCAGAUGUCUUAGUGCUACAGGGGCUGACAUUCACCCUACGCCCUGGCGAGGUGACGGCGCUGGUGGGACCCAAUGGGUCUGGGAAGAGCACAGUGGCUGCCCUGCUGCAGAAUCUGUACCAGCCCACCGGGGGACAGCUGCUGUUGGAUGGGAAGCCCCUUCCCCAAUAUGAGCACCGCUACCUGCACAGGCAGGUGGCUGCAGUGGGACAAGAGCCACAGGUAUUUGGAAGAAGUCUUCAAGAAAAUAUUGCCUAUGGCCUGACCCAGAAGCCAACUAUGGAGGAAAUCACAGCUGCUGCAGUAAAGUCUGGGGCCCAUAGUUUCAUCUCUGGACUCCCUCAGGGCUAUGACACAGAGGUAGACGAGGCUGGGAGCCAGCUGUCAGGGGGUCAGCGACAGGCAGUGGCGUUGGCCCGAGCAUUGAUCCGGAAACCGUGUGUACUUAUCCUGGAUGAUGCCACCAGUGCCCUGGAUGCAAACAGCCAGUUACAGGUGGAGCAGCUCCUGUACGAAAGCCCUGAGCGGUACUCCCGCUCAGUGCUUCUCAUCACCCAGCACCUCAGCCUGGUGGAGCAGGCUGACCACAUCCUCUUUCUGGAAGGAGGCGCUAUCCGGGAGGGGGGAACCCACCAGCAGCUCAUGGAGAAAAAGGGGUGCUACUGGGCCAUGGUGCAGGCUCCUGCAGAUGCUCCAGAAUGAAAGCCUUCUCAGACCUGCGCACUCCAUCUCCCUCCCUUUUCUUCUCUCUGUGGUGGAGAACCACAGCUGCAGAGUAGGCAGCUGCCUCCAGGAUGAGUUACUUGAAAUUUGCCUUGAGUGUGUUACCUCCUUUCCAAGCUCCUCGUGAUAAUGCAGACUUCCUGGAGUACAAACACAGGAUUUGUAAUUCCUUACUGUAACGGAGUUUAGAGCCAGGGCUGAUGCUUUGGUGUGGCCAGCACUCUGAAACUGAGAAAUGUUCAGAAUGUACGGAAAGAUGAUCAGCUAUUUUCAACAUAACUGAAGGCAUAUGCUGGCCCAUAAACACCCUGUAGGUUCUUGAUAUUUAUAAUAAAAUUGGUGUUUUGUA